ACCUCCUUGCCCAGAGAGACAGGCAACGUAGACCAUGGGUUCCCGCUGUGCCAAGCUCAACACAGGCCAGAGCCCAGGCCACAGCCCAGGCCACAGCACGGGCCAUGGCCGGGGCCACGAAUCCUCCAUGAAAAAGCUCAUGGCCUGUGUGAGUCAGGAUAACUUCUCCUUGUCAUCAGCGGGCGAGGAAGAGGAGGAAGAGGAGGAGGAGGGGGAAGAGGAGGAGAAAGAAGAGCUGCCGGUGCAGGGCAAGCUGCUGCUGCUGGAGCCUGAGCGGCAGGAGGAGGGCCACAAGGACAACGCCGAGGCCCAGCAGAGCCCCGAGCCCAAGCGGACACCCUCCUGACCCGCAACGAAGGCCCAGGAAGGGACGCCCACUGCUGCUCCGGCGACAGUGUUCAGAGAAGAGUCAAUAAAAAGUCUCUGAGGAA